ACGUCCUUAGGGUCCCUGAGCAGCCGGGUCCCCACGGCCCUCGGCGACCCGGGGUCCCCGGGAUGGAGCGAGGCUCUGGGCCUUCAGCAGACGCCGGGGCCCCAGACGCCCCUGAACCGAGCUCCAGAGACAUCCGAGCCCAGGCUCCUAGAGAACCGCCCCCCGCCGGGUGCGUCCGAGUCAGGGCUCCCCCGAAGGCGGGGACGUCGGGCGAGAAGCAACUGCAAGGACUCGCGUGAAGAAGCCACCGGGAAUCAUGGCGGCCGCGCUCAGAGGGACGGCUUUGCACGCAAGCUGUAUUUUUCUUCAACUCCUCUGUGUUUUUCAGAUCUUCUGUAGAAGUGUCUGUAGUGACCAUCAGAAAAACAAUCUGAAAGAAAGACAGGAAUUGCCACCGACCCCAGGGCUGCAUUUAUUGCUGGACAUUUGUCACGGUCUGAGCCGUGUGGACCGGCCCCGCUCAGCCAGAGCCAGGAGGGCUACGAGGGGAGGCGGGGCAGGGUUUGGGGACGAUUUCUCUCCGACCGAAGGAGUAAUGGGGCCAUCACGUAGGCAAGGUCAAAGGACGAUGUGGCGGUUGCAGGGUGACCCGAGGUCACGUAGGCAAGGUCAAAGGACGAUGUGGCGGUUGCAGGGUGACCCGAGGUCACGUAGGGAAGGUCAAAGGACGAUGUGGUGGUUGCAGGGUGACCCGAGGUCACGUAGGCAAGGUCAAAGGACGAUGUGGGGGUUGCAGGGUGACCCGAGGUCACGUAGGGAAGGUCAAAGGACGAUGUGGCGGUUGCAGGGUGACCCGAGGUCACGUAGGCAAGGUCAAAGGACGAUGUGGCGGUUGCAGGGUGACCCGAGGUCACGUAGGGAAGGUCAAAGGACGAUGUGGCGGUUGCAGGGUGACCCGAGGUCACGUAGGGAAGGUCAAAGGACGAUGUGGGGGUUGCAGGGUGACCCGAGGUCACGUAGGCAAGGUCAAAGGACGAUGUGGCGGUUGCAGGGUGACCCGAGGUCACGUAGGGAAGGUCAAAGGACGAUGUGGGGGUUGCAGGGUGACCCGAGGUCACGUAGGGAAGGUCAAAGGACGAUGUGGGGGUUGCAGGGUGACCCGAGGUCAUGUAGGCAAGGUCAAAGGACGAUGUGGCGGUUGCAGGGUGACCCGAGGUCAUGUAGGCAAGGUCAAAGGACGAUGUGAGGGUUGCAGGGUGACCCGAGGCCAGCAGUCCUUUGCAGAGUGGAUGAGCUUUCAGUGAGGGGUGAAGUGUGGAAUGGGACUCGCUGACGAAAGCCCACUCCUCCCUGGGCCAGGAGGGGCGCGGGGCCCAGGGCCGGUGUGGCUGGACGGGGGCCUCCCAGGUGGACGGGCAGGGGGGCUCUGAGAGCAGCUGCCGGGAUGGGAGGCGGAUGCGUCUGCCUGCUCUGUCCAGGCCUGGGGCCUGUUCCCACCAGGACGUGCCGGAAAGAGGCUCUUGCUCUGUGGGAAAAUCAUUCUGCUCCUCUUUCCUGUACAGCCCUGAGGCAGAGCCCGCACUGCGGUUUCCUUAGUUGGGAGCUGUGGUUGUGAGGAGCCCCCAGUCUCUAUCGUUCAGGGAUCCCCUUGACCUCAGUAAAAGCCCCCCUUAAGUCCACCAACCUUCUGAGAGCCUCCACUUGGCUCUGGUGGGGCAGUGCCCUGGAAGAGAGGUUUGGGGCUGCUGAUCCUGGCCAAGGGUCUUCCAGAAUGACGCUACUCAAUGUCCAGGAAUCAUAGGAGCCCAGUGUCUUGGCCUCACCAGGCUCUGUCACCCCCUCAACCCUGUGGCCCUGCAGUUCUUGAAGCUCAGGUCCCAGUCCUUGGUGACGACUGAACAACCCUGGCCUCUGCUUACUUCUUCAGGAAGCUGGAGCCUUACCCUGUUAGCAACGUCUUUCCAGCAUCCCUGGGAGAGAAGCAGCUUGCCAGCCCUCUGGGCUUGGUUUUAAACCUGCAACUGGAGCAUGGCCCAGAGGUAUGUGUGUGCCUGGGCCCUGCCCAGUGAGCGGGAGCCUGGCUCUGAGCAUCCUGCCUGAACAUCCCCAGCCCCUGGCGGGGCGACGCCACUGAGCAAGACACCCUGGGAGGUGAAUUCGGCAAUGGGAUGGCACAAAGGCCCAGCUUUCCCAUCUAAUGAGACAACUUCCACCGAACUCACAACACCGUAAACCUUCUAGAGACCAAGGCAACGUGCACCCAGAAAAUGUUUGGAUCAUUCUCUGCCUAGACUAAUUUAGAGGGAAGAUUCUCAGCGAAUCCAGCCCCCAACCCUUGAUUGUCUCCGGCAAGGAUGUUAGGUCCCCCUGUGCUUCAACAUGUUUGGAACAAGAACCAAUUCGUUUGUUCCUAACGUGACACCUGGAGGAGGCAGAGUCGCUGUGGAUGCCACGCCACCUCGCAGCCGUGACAGCUAAUGACGCCUGCAGUCCCCACCAUGGUCCCUGCCUCAUCCUCUGUGCCGUUGUCUUGUGUGUUCCAUUUAUAUGAAUGGCAACAAAAGUAGAAACCAGGAAAGCAAAAUGGCUUCAGUGAGGCUGUUUUGUUUUGUUUUGUUUUUCUUCUUCAACCUGGGAAAUUCAGGUCAAUAAAAGUGUAACAGAAAGAUGAGAAGAAA